GUUUACUGCUCGGUUAACUUCACUACAGGAAGUCUUCCAUGUACACACAGACACAUGCCCUUAUUAGCUUUGUCAAUAUCUUAAUUCUGUUGCUGUACUACAUCAAGAAGUUGUCAAGUGUCCUGUCUGCCCCCUUCUUUAUGUUGAGGUGGGAGGUAUUGUUUUAUCUGUUUUGUUUGGUUGACUGACCUAUGAAACUAACCCACUAUUUGUAAGAGUGGAUUUUUUAGCAGGAGAAAGCUAUCUGGGUUUCAAAAAGUGAGGUAUCAAUCAACUUAAAAUAUUCUGCUUGUAGUUUAAAAGAAUCUCUUCUUAUAUUUAUAUAUUUUAGAAAUGCUAUUUUUAUUCAGUAGCUUUUAGUAUGUCCUCUUUUUUUUUUUUUCUCUAAGUGCCAUGUAGGGAGUAUACAGGUAUGACUGAAGUAAUCACUGCUUUUAAAGAAUUUUUACCUCUGUCUGGUAGAGGAGAUAAUAGAACCUGAGGUAAAGAGAGGUACAGGCAGGCACCUGUACCUGGUUUAAAAGCAACAAAAUCUCCAAAAUCUAUAAUGAUUCUUAUAUGGGUUUUGAGUGAAAGAGAAAUGGUAGUAUAGAAUACUUAGACUGCUAGUGCAAGUCUUUGCCCUGGUUCUGAUUUAACACAUUGUCAGAUCUCCUAUCAAUUCUCACUAUUAAUUUUUCUAAACUAUUUCCCAGCUUUUCUUGUUCCUUCCCCUGCCUCACAAGCUGGGGUGCUGGCUUUUGUAAGAAUAGAAUAAGAAGAUAGAGCAGAUAGGAGGUGGAGGAACAAGAGCUUUUAAUCUAGACAACGAGCAACCAGAUUAUGAUAUGGAUUCAGAAGAUGAGACUUUAUUAAAUAGACUUAACAGAAAGAUGGAAAUUAAGCCUUUGCAAUUUGAAAUUAUGAUUGACAGACUUGAAAAAGCCAGUUCUAAUCAGCUUGUAACACUUCAAGAAGCAAAACUGCUGCUAAACGAAGAUGAUUACCUUAUUAAAGCUGUAUAUGACUACUGGGUGAGAAAACGUAAAAACUGCAGGGGGCCAUCCCUCAUUCCUCAGAUAAAACAAGAGAAAAGAGAUGGCUCUACCAACAAUGACCCUUAUGUUGCCUUUCGGAGAAGAACAGAGAAAAUGCAAACUCGAAAGAAUCGUAAGAAUGAUGAAGCCUCUUAUGAAAAGAUGUUGAAACUGAGACGAGAAUUUAGUAGAGCCAUAACAAUUUUGGAAAUGAUUAAGAGAAGAGAGAAAACAAAACGAGAAUUAUUGCACUUAACCUUAGAAGUUGUGGAGAAAAGAUACCAUUUGGGAGACUAUGGUGGUGAAAUCCUUAAUGAAGUAAAAAUCAGUAGAUCAGAAAAAGAGUUAUAUGCCACUCCAGCAACUCUUCAUAAUGGAAAUCAUCACAAAGUUCAAGAAUGUAAAACUAAGCACCCUCAUCAUUUGUCUUUGAAAGAAGAGGCUUCUGAUGUGGUUCGUCAAAAGAAGAAGUACCCAAAGAAGCCUAAAGCAGAGGCUUUGAUAACAUCUCAGCAACCCACUCCUGAGACAUUGCCUGUGAUCAAUAAGAGUGACAUUAAGCAAUAUGAUUUUCACAGCUCAGAUGAAGAUGAAUUUCCACAGGUAUUGUCCCCAGUAUCAGAACCGGAAGAAGAAAAUGAUCCUGAUGGUCCCUGUGCUUUCAGAAGGCGGGCAGGAUGCCAGUAUUAUGCUCCUCGUUUGGACCAAGCUAACCAUUCAUGUGAAAAUUCAGAAUUGGCAGAUUUGGAUAAGUUGAGGUAUAGGCAUUGCCUUACAACACUUACAGUCCCAAGAAGAUGUAUAGGAUUUGCAAGGAGGCGAAUUGGCAGAGGUGGAAGGGUCAUAAUGGACCGAAUAUCCACAGAACAUGACCCAGUCCUGAAACAGAUAGACCCUGAAAUGCUGAAUAGUUUUUCAAGCUCUUCCCAAACUAUAGACUUUUCUUCUAAUUUCUCUCGGACCAAUGCUUCCAGUAAACAUUGUGAAAAUAGACUGUCUCUUUCUGAAAUAUUAAGCAAUAUCAGAUCAUGUCGACUACAGUGUUUCCAGCCAAGGCUACUAAAUUUACAGGACAGUGAUAGUGAAGAAUGUACCUCAAGAAAACCAGGGCAGACUGUGAACAAUAAAAGAGUUUCUGCAGCAUCUGUAGCUUUAUUGAACACCAGCAAGAAUGGCAUAUCAGUAACAGGGGGUAUCACAGAAGAGCAGUUUCAGACACAUCAGCAGCAGUUAGUUCAGAUGCAAAGGCAGCAACUUGCCCAGCUUCAGCAGAAACAGCAAUCUCAGCAUUCCUCGCAACAGACACAUCCAAAAGCACAGGGCUCAAGCACCUCUGACUGUAUGUCUAAAACACUUGACUCAGCCAGCGCCCACUUUGCUGCAUCUGCAGUGGUCAGUGCACCUGUUCCAAGUCGCAGUGAGGUAGCCAAGGAACAGAACACUGGCCACAACAACAUAAACGGUGUUGUCCAGCCUUCAGGAACCUCUAAAACAUUAUACUCCACCAAUAUGGCUUUAUCAUCCAGCCCAGGGAUUUCAGCUGUACAGCUUGUAAGGACAGUUGGCCACACCACUACAAACCACUUAAUCCCAGCAUUGUGCACAAGCAGUCCUCAGACACUUCCCAUGAACAAUUCCUGCCUGACAAAUGCAGUGCACCUCAAUAAUGUCAGUGUUGUUUCUCCAGUCAAUGUGCAUAUCAAUACACGGACUUCAGCACCAUCGCCAACAGCCUUAAAACUUGCCACAGUUGCUGCCAGUAUGGACAGAGUGCCAAAGGUUACUCCCAGCAGUGCCAUCAGCAGCAUAGCAAGAGAGAACCACGAACCAGAAAGAUUGGGCUUAAAUGGAAUAGCAGAGACAACAGUAGCUAUGGAAGUGACAUAACCUAAAACACGUGGCUCUGACCUGUGCUGAUGGUGUGCAGUCAUUCAUAUUCCAGCUGAAUGCAAAAGGCAACACUCUGUGGAUCACAGAGUGUAACAAUGGACCUAAAUGGACUAUAGUAUAUUGGAUGUUAAAUCCAUAUAUGAUGUAUAUUUUGUAAAAUUGGGAAAAUCACUACCUUGUAAAAUAGUUUAUUUGUAUCAUCAAUAUUAUUUCUGUUACUUGAAUAGUAGAUAUUCAUCAUCAUGCUUUUGCACUUGAAUUUGCAACUGAAUGGAUUUUAAAAAAUAAUUCUUUAAUGGGAUCAUGAGCAUGAAAUGGGAUCCUGCAUCACUUGUUUUAACUAUUUAUUUUGCCAUGUUUACAUUUUGUAUCUUGUAAAAAUAAAUCCAACUUUGUGUCUAAAAAGUUAAAGAUUCAUAGCUAGGAAAUGAAAUUCUUGUAAUUUUUUUCUAAAGGAACUGUAAAGUUUUCACUUGGUUCAUUUUGUUUCACAAUUUGACUAGAUGGACUUUUUGGUAAAUACUUUAGUGGCAUUUCACUGUCAAAUAUGAAGUUCAAGGCAAAAUAGUAUUUUCUAUUACUGUGCAGGGGAAAGGGAUGGAUCGAUACAUGCAAAUUUAAUGUAGUAACUCACUUUUCCAUAUAUUUUGAAUGUAUAUUUCUAUUUAUGAUACCAAUUUAUAAAAAAUAAUUACACAGAAAAAAUGGAAUAGGAAAAAUUAUGCAUCUAGCACAUUUAAACUGUGCAAAUAUGAAAAUUUUUCGAGGAUUACAUUUUAUCUGAAGGCUGCAUAUUUUAACUGGCUUUAAAACUGUAACACAUCACAUAAAAGAUACUUUACCAGGUAUGUAUUGCAUUAUAUCAUUGCAAUAAUUAUUGGAAGUCUAGAUAUCGAGCCAUCCCAGGUGUUGGGCGGGGGGAGGGUUGUGGCAAGAUUGUCUUUUCAAUUUUGGAGAGUUUUCCUGUGGCUACAAGGCAAGUAACGGGUUGGAAAAAGUCUGACUGUAAGCGUUGGACACCUUCAUAGUGUAGUGUUUUAGUGACUUUUUUUAUACGGUUCUUGUAAAUUAGAUACGUGUAGUGGUGUUUCAGAAUGUUUGUUUAUGCACUAGUUCAGACAACUUUCCCUGUUACUUGUUCUUGAUAAGUGAAAACUGCAGGGAAAUAAAAAAUACAUAUCAAAACAUG